AACGAGAGCGAGGCACCACUUAUAGGGGUGGGCCAGGUAGGUUUCCCGGGGGAGCUGGCAUUGGAAUAGGCUUCUUCGCCUGCUCGGUGUCAAGACCCCGCAGGAGAUGGCGGAUUCAUUCAGGAAGCAGCCGCUCCGGGAAGCCUUAGCCAAGGGUCUUCCGGAAAGACACCAGUCUUGAUCCUGGAGCCUCAAUCCCCGCUGACCCAGCACUUUGGUUUCCAUAGCAAUUGUCUCGUCGCAGAAAGGAAUCGCCUGUGCUGGGUCUUCAGACCUCAGCUCCAUGCCGCUGAGCAGCCCCACCCUGGCUCAACCCGUUACCCGCCCCGCCAGCAGGCCGGGGUCACUGCAGUCCCCACGUCGAAGCGGAAAAGGGAAGCCGCAAUGACACAGCCGACUAGGCCCUCGGUCACCUGUGACCAGGGAUCCUCCACGAUCGGCGGGACCGCCGCCCAGGCGACCACCAGUUCCAGCGCCACCUCGGGUUCGAACUACCAGCGCGAUAGACUCGGCCGCCGCCCAGAAAUCGGCGUAGGGGGUCAGCCGCAGAUCUGCUUUCCGCGGCCGAGGUCCGCGCAGCAGCCGGUGCUGUUCAGCUUAAUGAAUUCCAGUGAAGCAGCGAUGAAAAAAACUUUACCCAAGAGCCAUUUAUCUCGGGUGAUUAUUCAUGAUAACCGCAUCACACAACGAAUCUAUGAGAUGGAGGUGAGCGCUUUAGAGAAGACCAAGAAAAAGAUCAGCCACUACUAUGAACACCUGAAAAAAAAGUUCAUGACAGAGCAGCUCAGAAAGCUCGGGCGAUGGAGAGAGGAAUCCGUGAACAGCAACCGGUACUUAACCUUCGGGAUACCACCACCAGUUUAAACUCCAGUCUCCCAAGAAAGGCCAACCACCCUAGUUCUGGCAAAGGGAUCUGCCCCAGGGUCACGAUGACACCAGUGUGACCCGAGGAGAACUAGUAACUACAACCUACACAACUGUAGAACAAUAAACAGAAACCAGCAGACAGCGGAGCAUAAUAAA